AUGACUUCCUGGCACCACAGGGAAAAUCGGGUGCAAGCCCAGAAACUAUUUCCCCACCACCACUUGUUGAAAAACUGA